GAAUUUCCCACCAGGAUGAGUAUGAUUGGCUGUGAUUUUAGGUUAGUUUUUGUAAAUCUUGUGGGAAGUAUUUGUAUUUUACUUCCUGGAAUGGAGAUAGUAGGGGUGGAUGUAUUCCCAUUCUGUAAUGGAGCUACUUUGGUUUCUUCCAUUCUCUGGAUCUGAUGUGGUACUGGUUGCUUCUUUUUUUAAAGUGGAGCUCAUUACUGAAUUAAAGGGAAUUGUUUAAAUGAAUGAUGUCUGUACAUGAUUUUUUAAAUCACCCUAGGCAUCGUUCAAAAAAUAAAAUUGCAAGUCAUUAUGUCUAACCAGUUCUUAUUAAAGUUACGAAAAAUUUCAAACAUGCAAACAUUGAAUAGUAUAAUAAUCCCCCCACUUACCCAUCACCAGCUUUAAUAGUAUCAACUUGCACAUUCUAUUUCAUCUAUACUUCUGUUUGUUUGGUUUUUUUUAAUUUUUUUAAAUUGAGAUGGGGUUUCAUCGUGUUGCCUAGACUGGUCACAAACUCCUGGGCUCAAGCCAUCCUCCCUUCUUGGCCUCCCAAAGUGUUGGGAUUACAGGCGUGAGCCACCAGGCCCAGCCUGUUUCAUCUAUACUUCUAACCACUGCCCCCCUCAAUGGAUUAUAUUGGAAUAAAUCCCUGUCAUAUUUAUUUGUAAAAUACUUGUUUGUAUUUCUAAAAGGCAAGGGCUCUUUAAAUAUAAGAUCAAAACUAUUAUCACAACUGAAAAAAUUAACAGAUAUUUAAAAAUAUCAAAUAUAAAAUGUUCAGAUUUCUGAUUUUUUUUUAAGCUUUGUUUUUUUUCUUUUACAGUUUGUUUGAAUCAGGAUCCUGAGAAAGCACAUUUAUUGCAAAGCAUUGAUACAGCUGUUAAAUCUAUUUUAAUCUGCAGGUUCUGUCUUUUGUUUUUUUUUUCUUCCAAUUUAUUUGUUGAAGAAAUUGUCCUAUAUAUAGUUUCCCGCCCCCCAUAUUUGGGGAUUACAGCCCAGUAGUGGUGUCUAACCCAUUCUUGCUCAAUUAAAGACCCUGGAGGACCCAUUAUAAUGGAACAAUGGCUAUAAUCUCCUGUAUCCUAGUUGGAGUUGAUAGUGCUGUCAUAGGCACUAUCCUAAAAUAACUAGUCAUGGAUUCCUUUUUCUGUGGCAAAGUCUGAUUUGAUACCUGACUUCAGUUCCAUGUCUUGGCCUUGCUCAUUGCUCCACAUGAAAAGUAGGCCUCCUGGUGGAAGAAGCUAGUGUUUCCUAAUGACCUGAUUGUGCCUUUGGGGUUUUUCAUGCAUGGUUUCAAUUUCCUUAGGUGAUUUAGUUAUUUUUAUACUACUUUAUAAUGUUGCUUUUUAUUCUUUUGAUGUUAGUGUCUCAGCUGUUCUGACCCAUAACUUCUAAGCUAUUAAGACCUAAUAAUGAGUUCCUGGCUGUCAUACAGUUCUUGAAAUGGCAAUACUAAAACAGUUUUUGAGAGCUUCUACUUACAUGUUGAUUUUCAGCUAUUAUACACAACCUUAGUUUUCCUACUGUGAUUUUUCAUUUCAUUUCAUCUGAAAUUUAUGUUUCCUUAGCAUAAAGUCCUUUAAGGACUUUUAGGCUGCUUUAUGAUGAUCUCACUAUCUAUAAGGUUGAUAUUCAUAAGUACUUGGGCUUUUGGUGUUUUGCUGUAUUAUUCGUUGUUUCCUCAACGACUGGUUACUAGAUGUUUAUAUAUGUUAAUGUCAGGAAUAACUCAACUUUUAAGUCGUUUGAUGUUUCAUAGGUGGUGUUGUUAAAACUUGAUGUACUUGUUGACCAGCUUGGUCUUCUGGAUAUAGAAAUCCUUUCAGGUAGUGAAGAAGUGGCUCUAUGAGUAAAACAACUGUAGGUUUUGUUUGGGCUGUUAACCUGAGCAUUUUCAACUUUUAAGUUCUCUUUAAAAGUUUUUAGUCAUUUGGCUUUAAAAAUUACAGUUGGUGGCAUAGAAUGAUCCCAUAAUGUGAUUUUACAGAAAGUUGGAAUGUUUUAAUUUAUUAUGAAUGUACCAUUACGUGGAGAUUGGGAUUGUAGAUCUGAUUCAGUCUGGAUUGCUGAUUGAACUAGAUGAAUGUUAAAAUUCUUCAACUCUGAGAUUCUGAUGGUAUAAUCUUAGGUAUUGAAAGACAGCAGUUUUUCCUUUCAGUAGUCAUUAAGUAAAUGGUGACUAAAAGUAGGGAGAUGAAUUAUUCUGGAAUGACCUUUCACUAUAACCAUUUAGAUUUAAAAGAUUGAUGAGUCUGAGGAUACUGUCAUGAAUUUAUGUACCACCUUUAGCACAAUCCAGGUUUUAGGUCCUUGUGAUUAGAUAUCAGAGAUAAUUGCCCCAGAAGUGCGUGGGUAUAUUACAUUUGGUGGCUGUUAAUGUUUUGGAAUGAUUUUGGAAGAUUACUUUGGGUACAUUAUUUGCUAUGAUUAUUUUCUUAUAUUCCUGUCUAUUUUAUAGUGAGGCAUGUUUCUCCUGGUCUUUGCUUUUUUUUUUUUUUUUUUUAAACUUCCAAUAUUCUUUAUUACGGCAUUCUGACAAUUGAGUUCUUACAGGUGGAAAGACCUUUCAGCACAGCGAUUAAGAACAUGGACUCUGGAGCUAGAUUCACAGAGUUCAAGUUCUGACUCCCAUUUCUUACCAGGUGUGUCAUGUUGUGCAAAUUACUUAACUGCUUUGUGCCACACGGUCCUUCAUCUGUAAAAUGAUGAUAAUACUGCCUGCCUUAUAGAGUUCUGAAGAAAUUUAGCUGAGUUAAUGCAUAUAAAGUGCUUAGAACAAUGGUUCUGAAACUUUAGGGAACAUCAGAAUCACCUAGAGGACUUCCUAAAAGAUUGGCUGGUCCCCACUCCCAGAGUUUCUGAUUCUGUAGAUCUAGGAGGGGCCCCAGAUUUUGCAUUUCUGAUAAGUUCCCAGGUGAUACUUCUCUAUUUCCUGCAAAUUGGCAGCUGGAUCCAGAGACUUGAUAAAUUUCAGGUUCGUUCCCUUUGGCAAAUAUAUUGCGGGGGGGUGGGGUGGGGGGGUGUUCAUUCACAACAUUGAUUAUGUUACGAUGACUUGAAUUUUUUGGAUCCAUUAAUUUGUUGGGGGGCUACAAAAUGGUGACGUUCUGAUGCUAUCAUUUUGUUUUCAUCUGUUAGCUGGAAUAAUUUUGUUUCCCCUCAUCUUUUAUUUGGUUACUCAGCAAUAUAGUUUAUAUAGGAAGAGCAGGAUAAAUACUCAAUUUUUUAAAACAUUGCUUUCAAGAUGAUGAAUUGGUCCCCUGUCAUCUUCAAAAGGUUACACAUAUAAGUGUAUAUAUAACUAUGCAUCCAUAGAUGUAAACAUUUGAUGGGUUUCAAUACAUUGCAGUUCUGAUCCUUAGCGAAGUUCAAAUUGCCCUUCUUGUGGCUAGUGGAACUCUCUUAAAGUUGGCUCCUGAUUCUUACUGACAUGCUCUCUAGUAGUCUUUGAUAGCUUCCUUGCUAUCUGGUAUGUCAAGAUGUUUCCAGGCGCAUUCUUGUGCAUUUCUGCCCCAGACCUGGAAUUAGCUAAUGGGAUUAAGAUAAAAGGUGAAGUCAAAAGAAAUUCUGUUUUUGCCAAGGGUAGCUUGGAACUUUCUAUCAAGUUCCACUUUUCUCUUUCCACUUAACCUCCCUAGCCUGCCUCUUCAUUCUUCUCUACCUUUUUAUUAGAGUUAAGGUGGAAAGGUUUGAGAAGCCUUGAUAAUCAUAGGAAGAUCAUGGAGCCCAGGCAGUUCCGGAUUUGGGGCCUGGCCACUUACUAGGUCUGUCAGUUUGGGCAAGUUAACCUAUAUCAGUUAUGAUGUGGGGGGAAAUACCUUAUUCAUAUGGUUAUUGGAAUUAAAGAGAAAAUGUAAGGUGUUAGUACAUGGUAGGUGAUCAGUAGAUGGUAAUUUAUUUAAUGUACUAUUUUACUUAACUCCUUCAACAGCUCAGAGGUGGGCAGUCAGGGUGGUGAAAAUAAUGGCCAUUUAACAAAAUGUGUCUGGACCCUUUAGGUCUGUGUGGGAUCAUCAGUGGUGAGGCAGGAUAGGGUUUGUUCUUGAGUUAUUUUGGGUCUGAGACUUUGGCCAGUGAUAACUGAAUGUUCCAUAGAGUAGUUUUUCACUUUGGAACUCCUUAGGAGUCACAUUUAUACCCUCUGAAGGGUCUUAGCUAGUUCUGUAAUGUGUAUUACAUUGGUUACCUUGAUCUCUCUCCGUCUAUACUGGCCCCUCCUAUUCAAGGUGUUCAAGGUUCUGUUGUAACCUUAGUAACCUAUAAUAAGUAUUCCUAAUAGUCAUCAGUAUCACCACUGUUAACACAUUUGGGCAGCACCAUGCAUGGCAGGUCAGCAAACAGGUAAAUCUUAUUUUUUUAAACAUUACACAUAAUAUCUAAAGUAUAGUUUGUGGCAUGUAAUAAGUGCUGCUGAAUAAAUGGAAGUCAUUGUUCAGUUUUUAGCUUAAUAUAUCUUUUUUUUUCUUUUAACAUAACAUUUACUGAAUGUUGCUAAGUAUAAGGAGUAAGGGACAUAAAAUGAAUGAGACUUGGUCUCUGCCCUUGAGAAACUCACAGUCGAGUUAAGGACUGUGAAAUCAUGUUUAAAGUUCCUUAGCCUUUUCCUUUGUGUCAUCAUUUCUUCCCCUGCACUGUCUAUGCAUGAUAUAGCCUGUCCAUUGUUUCUCACAGCUUUCCUAAUUCUGUGUGCCUCCCCAGCCUUUGAGACUGCUGAUAUGUGAGAAAGCCAACAAUUGUCUUCUAUUAAUACAGGGUAAUAUCAAGAAAAACCUUUGGGCCAAUAUUGGAUUUCAGAGUGGCAUGUGCAGUUGACAUUACAAUACCAGUUUAUGGUCUUUAGAUGGGCCUGUACACCUGGGCUCCAGCCUCUUUCCUGUGCCUUUAAACUGCCUUACUUCCAUCUUUCCUCCCCUAUACCCUACCCUUAAUGUACUUGGUACAUAAAAAUAGAGGCUCCCAUACCCAGGUAGUGAUCAAGUACAAUGUAAAGAAACAGCUGUACUUCAUAUAAACUAGGAUUCGAGUGGGCCUAGGGUAUAUCACUAAAUUUCCAUUCUUAUCUAUAAAACAGUAAUCGGAAAGCCUAUUUCAUAGGUUGCUGUGAGCAUUAAAGCGAGAUGAUGUAUUUUUAAAUGCUUGUAAAGUACGAAGAUAAGGUCAUUAUAAUUUAUAUAAAAUACUUAGUAGCUAUGUUACUUGGGGCAAAUUACCUCAUCACUGAGCCAGUUUCCUCAUCCUUUAAAUGAAGAUGGUGAUAUUCAUUUAACAAAUAUUUAUUGAGGACGUAGUCAUUGCAGCUACAUCCUGGGAAUACAAAGAUAAGUGACUGGAGAAUGUAGGACAGUGUGGUCUAGGGGAAGGAGACUUGCAAAUCACACAAAAGGGUCAGUAUGGUAAUAUGAGGAAUGAACAAAAUGUGCUAUAGCAGUUUACAAGAAGGCAUCAGAGAAUGUCACAGAGUUUUGUUAGGGUUAAGCAAGAUAAAUGAAAAGUACUUCAUGAAUUCAAAAAUGCUAUACAAAUAAGUUAGUUAAACGUACCCCAAAUGAAUCAAUAGUCUCAAACCAUUAUUGUUUCAUUUCUUCACAAGACUUACUCUUUAGAUGCAUUUAUUUCUUUGAGCUAGAUUUUAUGACCUCCUUAAGGGUAACCUGUAGUAGAGUAUCCUGAAAGUUAAUGCUUUUGUCUAAAAGGAUUUUUUUCAUCCAUUUUAUCAUUUUCUAGUUUUUAAUCACUGAAUUCAGGAAAAACUAGAAAAUGUGUGCAUAUUUGGGGAGAGGAUAUACAUAAUUCCACCACAAUGUUUAGUCACUGUUAACAUUUUGGUGUAUUCACAUCUUAAUGAUAAGGGUAGUGUUUAAGGAAUAAGAAAAGAAAUCUAGUAGGAAAUUUUAAGGAUAGGCAUUUCCCAGAAUAGGAAACUAAAAACGUCCACUAACAAGAAAUGGUACUCAAACUAAUAAUCAGAAAUGCAAAUUUAAAUAAGGUCAUUUUUAGUCAUUAGAUUGAUAAAAAAUAAUUUGAUAAUAUCAAGUCAUCGUAAAAGGUAUAAGGAAGAGUCUGGCCUUAUAAUACUGCCUACAAGUGGCGUAAAUUGAUACAGCUAUUUUGGAGGCAAUUUUGGCAAGUUGCAAGAGAGUACAUACUAUGUGAUGCUAUUUAUGUUUUAAAAAAAACCAUGGCAAACUGACAACUUUAUUUGGGAGGAGGGAUCGUGGGGAACUUUACCUUUUUCUGUAAUAUGUGCAUUUCUACUUCUGAAAAAUAUACUGAGAAGUACAGAGAAUAAUACAACAAUCCCUGUCCCUACCCCCACUCCAGAAUUGAUCAUUUUUAACAUUUAUUUUUGCCUUACAUUUUUUUGUGGAGUUGGAAGUAACACAAGUUGAGUGUCCCUAAUCCAAAAUUCAAAAUGCCCCAAAAUGAGUUUCAACACGAUGCCACAAGUGGAAAAUUCUACGCCUAAGUACUUAACACUUUGUUUCAUGAGCAGAAUUAUUAAAAAUAUUGUAUAGGGUACAACGAACAUUAUUUGGGUGAUGGUUACACUAAAUGUCUAGACUUCACUACUGCACAAUAUACCCAUGUAACAGAACUGUACUUGUGCCACCUAAAUUUAUACGAGAAAUUGUGUAAAAUUACCUUCAGGCUGUAUGUAUAAGGUGUGUAUGGAACAUGAAUGGAUUUCAUGUUUAAACUUGAGCCGCAUCCUCAAGAUGUCUCAUGAUGUAUAGGCAGAUAUUCAAGAAUCUGAAAUCUGAAAUCCUGCUGGUCCCAAGCACUGGAUAGGAGAUACUUAACCUGUAUAGGUAAACAGGAGAUACUUUUUUAAUACCCAGCAUUCCCUUCCCCCCUUACAAUCAGUACAAUGAAUUGCUUGAAUUUUUCUACUGUGAGAAUGGUAUAAAUUAUGAAUGUAAGUAAAAGUUCAAAACCGAUGUGGUGGCCACACAAAAACCUAUUAUUAAAUAAUAUUAAAUUUGUACAGUAUUUUAGAGUUUGUAAGAAGCAUUCUGAUUUUAGUAAGAAUGCUUUGGGAAUAGAACUUUUUUUCGUUUGCUCAUUUUCUUGUUAACUCUUGUUUGAAAACGUUUUCCUGAAUUUGUUUUUAAGUAAUCUUCAUGACUGUAGAAUUAUACAUGGCUUAUUGUUGAAAAAUACAGAUAAACAGACAAAUUUCCGCAAACCCCAAACUCACAGAUAAAAUACUCUUAACAUUUUGGUAUGCAGUAUCUUCUUCGAAGGCUUUUCUUAACUGCUCUGUAGCCAUAUUAUAUAUUUUUUCAGAAAUGCUCUUUUUAAAAUGUAAUUCAUUACCUCCCUUCCAGCUUUCAAUUUUGUAUGAAAAAUUUCAAACAAAAAUGCUGAAAACAUAGCACAAUGAACAUCUGUAUACCAUCAGCUGGAUCCAACAAUUAAGUAUUUGCCAUAUUAGAUUUAUAUGUACAGAUGUGUGUUUAAUUUUUCUCAACAUUAGAAGUAAGGAUGACACUUUAUCCUUAAAUCUUUCAGCUGCAUGUCUUAAGAAUGAGGACAUCUCAGCCGGGCGCAGUGGCUCACACCUGUAAUCUGAGCACUUUGGGAGGCCAAGAUCGUAAAGCUGAAAAUUGAAAUCAUGAAAGUAGACAGGACUAAACUGAAGAAGACACCUACUGAGGCUCCUGCAGACUGCAGAGCCUUAAUAGACAAACUCAAAGUUUGUAAUGAUGAGCAACUUCUCUUGGAACUGCAGCAGAUCAAAACAUGGAACAUUGGAAAGUGCGAGUUAUAUCACUGGGUGGACCUGUUGGACCGCUUCGAUGGAAUACUGGCAGAUGCUGGACAGACAGUGGAGAAUAUGUCAUGGAUGCUCGUAUGUGAUAGGCCAGAAAGAGAGCAACUGAAAAUGCUUCUCUUGGCUGUGUUGAACUUCACAGCCUUGCUCAUUGAGUACAGCUUUUCCCGGCAUCUGUACAGUUCCAUAGAGCAUUUGACAACUUUAUUGGCUUCCUCUGAUAUGCAAGUGGUGCUGGCAGUCCUCAAUCUCCUAUAUGUAUUUAGCAAAAGAUCAAACUACAUCACUCGUCUGGGAUCUGACAAGAGGACCCCGCUGCUAACUCGGCUACAACAUUUGGCAGAGAGCUGGGGUGGAAAGGAGAAUGGCUUUGGACUUGCAGAAUGUUGCAGAGACUUGCAUAUGAUGAAAUAUCCACCCAGUGCAACUACACUACACUUUGAAUUCUAUGCAGAUCCUGGGGCCGAGGUCAAAAUUGAGAAAAGGACAACUAGUAACACACUACAUUAUAUUCACAUAGAGCAACUUGACAAGAUUUCAGAAAGCCCUUCUGAAAUCAUGGAAUCUCUUACCAAAAUGUACAGCAUUCCUAAGGAUAAGCAGAUGCUGUUAUUUACACACAUACGACUGGCCCAUGGCUUUUCUAAUCACAGGAAGCGAUUGCAGGCAGUUCAGGCCAGACUGCAUGCAAUAUCUAUAUUAGUGUAUUCCAAUGCCUUGCAGGAAUCAGCAAACAGUAUCUUGUAUAAUGGCUUGAUAGAGGAGUUGGUAGAUGUCCUUCAGAUAACGGAUAAGCAGCUUAUGGAGAUUAAAGCAGCUUCUUUACGAACAUUAACAUCAAUUGUCCACUUGGAGAGAACUCCCAAACUCAGCAGUAUUAUUGACUGUACUGGAACUGCCUCCUACCAUGGAUUUUUGCCAGUGCUUGUAAGGAACUGUAUCCAGGCCAUGAUUGAUCCUUCCAUGGAUCCAUACCCUCACCAGUUUGCCACUGCUCUCUUCUCUUUUUUAUACCAUCUGGCCAGCUACGAUGCUGGUGGUGAAGCCUUGGUCUCCUGUGGAAUGAUGGAAGCCUUAUUGAAGGUCAUAAAGUUUCUUGGCGAUGAACAGGACCAGAUAACAUUUGUCACCAGAGCCGUCAGAGUGGUUGACCUUAUCACCAACCUGGAUAUGGCAGCUUUUCAAUCCCAUAGUGGACUUUCUAUCUUCAUUUAUAGACUUGAGCAUGAAGUAGAUUUGUGCCGAAAAGAAUGUCCGUUUGUGAUCAAGCCAAAGAUCCAGAGACCCAAUACUACACAAGAAGGAGAGGAAAUGGAAACUGAUAUGGAUGUUGCAGAUGUGGCUAUGGAAAGCAGUCCAGGCUCAUCCAUCUCUAUGGAGCACAGGCUGGAUGUUGAAUUAAGGGCAUCAGGUUCCAGCAGCAGCACUAACAUCUCUUCUGGCCCCAGCCCUGGUCCCAGUCCCGGCCCCGGCACCGGCCCUGGCCCCGGCCCCGGCCCCGGCCCCGGCCCUGGCCCCGGCCCCGGCCCCGGUCCUGGUCCCGGCCCUGGCCCCGGCCCUGGCCCUGGCCCCCGUCCUGGAGUCCAGUGUAUUCCACAACGAGCAGCACUUCUGAAAUCCAUGUUGAAUUUCCUCAAGAAGGCCAUCCAAGACCCUGCUUUCUCAGAUGGCAUACGACAUGUGAUGGAUGGUUCUCUGCCUACCUCCCUGAAACACAUCAUCAGCAAUGCAGAAUACUAUGGCCCAUCACUCUUCCUCCUAGCUACUGAAGUGGUGACUGUGUUUGUAUUUCAAGAACCAUCACUGCUCUCCUCACUCCAGGACAAUGGAUUGACAGAUGUCAUGCUGCAUGCACUGCUUAUCAAAGAUGUUCCUGCUACCCGUGAAGUCCUUGGCUCCCUCCCAAAUGUAUUCAGUGCACUCUGUUUGAAUGCCCGAGGUCUUCAGUCUUUUGUUCAGUGUCAGCCUUUUGAACGCCUCUUCAAAGUUCUUCUGUCUCCAGAUUACCUCCCAGCCAUGCGGAGGAGGAGAAGUUCUGAUCCCCUUGGGGAUACUGCAUCCAACCUGGGGAGUGCUGUCGAUGAGCUCAUGAGACAUCAGCCCACCCUUAAAACAGAUGCAACGACUGCCAUCAUCAAGUUACUUGAAGAAAUCUGUAAUCUUGGAAGGGACCCCAAAUACAUCUGUCAGAAGCCAUCAAUCCAGAAGGCAGAUGGCACUGCCACUGCUCCUCCCCCAAGGUCUAAUCAUGCCGCAGAAGAAGCCUCUAGUGAGGAUGAGGAGGAAGAGGAAGUACAGGCCAUGCAGAGCUUUAAUUCUACCCAGCAAAAUGAAACUGAGCCUAAUCAGCAGGUUGUUGGUACAGAGGAACGUAUUCCUAUUCCCCUCAUGGAUUACAUCCUUAAUGUGAUGAAAUUUGUGGAAUCUAUUCUGAGCAACAAUACAACAGAUGACCACUGCCAGGAAUUUGUGAAUCAGAAAGGACUGUUGCCUUUGGUUACCAUUUUGGGUCUUCCCAAUCUGCCCAUUGACUUUCCCACAUCUGCUGCCUGUCAGGCUGUUGCAGGUGUCUGCAAAUCCAUAUUGACACUGUCACAUGAACCCAAAGUCCUUCAAGAGGGUCUCCUUCAGUUGGACUCCAUCCUCUCCUCCCUGGAGCCCUUACACCGCCCCAUUGAAUCCCCUGGGGGCUCAGUGUUGUUGCGAGAACUGGCUUGCGCAGGCAAUGUUGCUGAUGCUACCCUCUCAGCCCAGGCCACACCUCUGCUGCAUGCACUCACUGCUGCCCAUGCCUACAUCAUGAUGUUUGUUCAUACUUGCAGAGUUGGACAGAGUGAAAUUCGUUCCAUCUCCGUAAACCAGUGGGGCUCUCAAUUGGGUCUGAGUGUUUUGAGCAAGCUGAGCCAGUUAUACUGUUCCCUGGUGUGGGAAAGCACUGUCCUCCUCUCUCUGUGUACCCCAAACAGCCUACCAUCUGGGUGUGAAUUUGGCCAGGCAGAUAUGCAGAAACUGGUUCCAAAGGAUGAGAAGGCAGGUACGACCCAGGGCGGAAAAAGAUCAGAUGGGGAACAGGAUGGAGCAGCUGGAAGUAUGGAUGCUUCUACCCAGGGCUUAUUAGAAGGCAUUGGGCUAGAUGGUGACACAUUGGCUCCCAUGGAGACAGAUGAACCUACUGCUUCAGACUCUAAGGGCAAAUCUAAAAUCACACCAGCAAUGGCUGCCAGAAUUAAGCAAAUCAAGCCUUUGUUAUCAGCUUCCUCCAGAUUAGGCCGAGCACUUGCUGAGCUAUUUGGACUUCUUGUUAAACUUUGUGUGGGAUCUCCUGUCCGCCAGAGAAGGAGCCAUCAUGCUGCCAGCACCACUACAGCACCGACACCUGCCGCGCGAUCAACAGCCUCAGCUCUCACUAAGCUCUUGACUAAGGGGUUAUCUUGGCAGCCCCCACCAUAUACACCUACUCCCCGAUUCAGGCUGACAUUCUUCAUCUGUUCAGUUGGUUUCACAUCCCCAAUGCUGUUUGAUGAGAGGAAGUAUCCCUACCACCUCAUGCUGCAAAAAUUUCUCUGCUCCGGAGGCCACAAUGCUCUUUUUGAAACUUUCAACUGGGCUCUGUCCAUGGGAGGUAAAGUUCCUGUUUCUGAGGGAUUGGAACACUCAGACUUGCCUGAUGGCACAGGAGAAUUCCUAGAUGCCUGGCUUAUGCUGGUGGAGAAGAUGGUGAAUCCCACCACGGUGCUUGAAUCUCCACAUUCGCUGCCUGCCAAAUUGCCUGGAGGUGUCCAGAACUUUCCCCAGUUCAGUGCACUGCGCUUCCUUGUGGUAACUCAGAAAGCAGCCUUUACUUGCAUCAAAAACUUAUGGAACCGGAAACCCCUGAAGGUAUAUGGUGGACGAAUGGCUGAAUCGAUGCUGGCCAUUCUAUGCCACAUCCUCCGAGGAGAACCUGUGAUUCGAGAGAGACUAAGCAAGGAGAAGGAGGGGUCUCGAGGAGAAGAGGAUACAGGGCAAGAGGAAGGUGGCUCCCGCCGGGAACCUCAAGUCAACCAGCAACAACUGCAACAGCUCAUGGACAUGGGCUUCACAAGGGAACAUGCAAUGGAGGCACUGUUGAACACCAGCACCAUGGAGCAGGCCACAGAGUACCUUUUAACCCACCCUCCUCCAAUCAUGGGAGGAGUUGUUCGGGAUCUCAGCAUGUCUGAAGAGGACCAGAUGAUGAGAGCAAUUGCUAUGUCUCUGGGACAGGAUAUUCCAAUGGAUCAAAGGGCAGAGUCACCUGAGGAAGUUGCUUGCCGGAAGGAGGAAGAGGAACGGAAAGCUCGGGAAAAGCAGGAGGAGGAAGAGGCUAAAUGUCUAGAGAAGUUCCAGGAUGCUGACCCGUUGGAACAAGAUGAGCUCCACACUUUCACAGAUACUAUGUUGCCAGGCUGCUUCCACCUUCUUGAUGAGCUGCCAGACACAGUAUACCGUGUGUGUGACCUGAUCAUGACAGCAAUCAAACGUAAUGGAGCAGAUUAUCGUGACAUGAUUCUGAAGCAAGUAGUCAAUCAGGUGUGGGAAGCUGCUGAUGUAUUGAUCAAAGCUGCUCUUCCCCUGACAACAAGUGACACAAAAACCGUGUCAGAGUGGAUAAGUCAGAUGGCCACACUGCCCCAGGCCUCCAAUUUGGCUACUAGAAUCUUGCUUUUAACGCUACUUUUUGAGGAGUUGAAGCUACCUUGUGCUUGGGUGGUUGAAUCAAGUGGCAUCCUUAAUGUCCUAAUCAAACUCUUGGAAGUGGUUCAGCCCUGCCUCCAGGCAGCCAAGGAGCAGAAGGAAGUCCAGACCCCAAAGUGGAUCACACCAGUGUUGCUCCUGAUUGAUUUCUAUGAAAAGACAGCCAUCUCCUCAAAAAGGAGAGCCCAGAUGACUAAGUACCUGCAAUCCAACAGCAACAACUGGCGCUGGUUUGAUGAUCGCUCUGGGCGUUGGUGUAGUUACAGUGCAAGCAACAAUAGCACUAUUGAUUCUGCCUGGAAAUCUGGAGAGACAAGCGUGCGAUUCACUGCAGGCCGAAGAAGAUACACGGUCCAAUUCACUACAAUGGUGCAGGUUAAUGAGGAAACAGGGAACCGACGCCCUGUGAUGCUGACUCUCCUCAGGGUACCUCGGCUGAAUAAAAAUUCAAAAAACAGCAAUGGACAGGAACUAGAGAAGACGCUGGAAGAAAGCAAAGAAAUGGAUAUCAAACGUAAAGAAAAUAAAGGCAAUGAUACCCCUUUGGCCCUAGAGAGUACAAACACUGAAAAGGAGACAAGCCUGGAGGAAACAAAAAUCGGGGAGAUCCUGAUCCAGGGCUUGACAGAAGAUAUGGUGACUGUUUUAAUCCGGGCCUGCGUGAGCAUGCUGGGAGUCCCUGUGGACCCAGAUACUUUGCAUGCCACCCUUCGUCUCUGUCUGAGGCUCACCCGGGACCACAAAUAUGCCAUGAUGUUUGCAGAACUGAAGAGUACCCGCAUGAUCUUGAAUUUGACCCAGAGCUCAGGCUUCAAUGGGUUUACUCCCCUGGUCACCCUUCUCUUAAGACACAUCAUUGAGGACCCCUGUACCCUUCGUCAUACCAUGGAAAAGGUUGUUCGCUCAGCAGCUACAAGUGGAGCUGGUAGCACUACCUCUGGUGUUGUGUCUGGCAGCCUCGGCUCUCGGGAGAUCAACUACAUCCUUCGUGUCCUUGGGCCAGCCGCAUGCCGCAAUCCAGACAUAUUCACAGAAGUGGCCAACUGCUGUAUCCGCAUCGCCCUUCCUGCCCCUCGAGGCUCAGGAACUGCUUCAGAUGAUGAAUUUGAGAAUCUUAGAAUUAAAGGCCCUAAUGCUGUACAGCUGGUGAAGACCACCCCUUUGAAGCCCUCACCUCUGCCUGUCAUCCCUGAUACUAUCAAGGAAGUGAUCUAUGAUAUGCUGAAUGCUCUGGCUGCAUACCAUGCUCCAGAGGAAGCAGAUAAAUCUGAUCCUAAACCUGGGGUUAUGACCCAAGAGGUUGGCCAGCUCCUGCAAGACAUGGGUGAUGAUGUAUACCAGCAGUACCGGUCACUUACGCGUCAGAGCAGUGACUUUGAUACGCAGUCAGGUUUUUCCAUUAAUAGUCAGGUCUUUGCUGCAGAUGGUGCCUCCACUGAGACUUCCGCAUCUGGGACCUCCCAAGGAGAGGCUUCAACUCCAGAGGAGUCUCGAGAUGGGAAGAAAGAUAAAGAAGGGGACCGGGCCUCUGAGGAAGGCAAACAGAAAGGCAAGGGCAGCAAACCUUUAAUGCCUACCUCCACUAUCCUUCGUCUUCUGGCAGAGUUGGUGAGGUCCUAUGUUGGUAUUGCUACCCUGAUUGCCAACUACAGCUACACUGUGGGCCAGUCUGAACUGAUCAAAGAGGACUGCAGUGUGCUAGCUUUUGUUCUGGACCACCUGCUCCCACAUACCCAGAAUGCAGAAGACAAGGACACCCCUGCCUUGGCCCGCCUGUUCCUCGCAAGCCUGGCUGCUGCAGGGAGUGGCACAGAUGCCCAGGUGGCCCUAGUGAAUGAAGUAAAAGCAGCCCUUGGACGGGCACUGGCUAUGGCUGAGAGUACAGAGAAACAUGCCAGGCUUCAGGCAGUGAUGUGUAUCAUCAGUACUAUCAUGGAGUCCUGCCCCUCCACCUCCAGCUUCUACAGCAGUGCCACAGCGAAGACCCAGCACAAUGGCAUGAACAACAUCAUUCGGCUUUUCCUGAAGAAGGGACUGGUUAAUGACCUGGCCAGAGUACCUCACAGCUUAGACCUGUCCAGUCCCAACAUGGCCAACACAGUCAAUGCUGCUCUGAAGCCUUUGGAAACACUUUCCCGGAUUGUGAACCAGCCCAGUAGCCUUUUUGGCAGCAAGAGUGCUUCUAGCAAGAACAAGUCUGAGCAGGAUGCCCAAGGAGCCUCUCAAGAUUCCAGUAGCAACCAGCAGGACCCAGGCGAGCCUGGGGAAGCAGAAGUGCAGGAGGAGGAUCAUGAUGUCACUCAGACAGAGGUGGCAGAUGGGGAUAUCAUGGAUGGGGAGGCUGAAACCGACUCAGUGGUGAUUGCUGGGCAGCCUGAGGUGCUCAGUUCACAAGAGAUGCAGGUUGAGAAUGAGCUGGAGGACCUGAUAGAUGAGUUGCUUGAGAGGGAUGGCGGAUCUGGGAACAGUACAAUUAUAGUGAGCAGAAGUGGAGAGGAUGAAUCACAAGAGGACGUGCUGAUGGAUGAAGCUCCUUCCAACCUCAGCCAAGCUUCCACCUUGCAGGCCAACCGAGAAGAUUCCAUGAAUAUCCUGGACCCUGAGGAUGAGGAGGAGCACACUCAGGAAGAGGACAGCAGUGGCAGUAACGAGGAUGAGGAUGAUAGUCAGGAUGAAGAGGAGGAGGAGGAGGAAGAUGAGGAAGAUGAUCAGGAGGAUGAUGAAGGUGAAGAGGGAGAUGAAGACGAUGACGACGAUGGCUCUGAGAUGGAAUUGGAUGAGGAUUAUCCUGAUAUGAACGCUUCUCCCUUGGUCCGAUUUGAGCGCUUUGACCGGGAGGAUGAUCUCAUCAUUGAGUUUGACAACAUGUUCUCCAGUGCUACAGACAUCCCCCCAUCCCCAGGAAAUAUCCCUACCACCCAUCCACUGAUGGUGCGCCAUGCAGACCACAGUUCUCUGACACUGGGCAGUGGCUCUUCAACAACUCGUCUCACCCAGGGCAUCGGGCGCAGUCAGAGGACCCUAAGGCAGCUGACGGCCAAUACUGGCCACACCAUUCAUGUUCACUACCCUGGGAAUCGCCAGCCCAACCCUCCUCUUAUACUGCAGAGGUUGCUUGGUCCCUCAGCUGCUGCUGACAUCCUUCAGCUGAGCAGCAGCCUUCCCCUACAAAGCCGGGGUCGGGCCCGCCUCCUGGUAGGCAACGAUGACGUCCACAUCAUCGCCCGUUCUGAUGAUGAGCUGCUGGAUGACUUUUUCCAUGAUCAGAGCACAGCUACCAGCCAAGCAGGAACCCUGUCCAGCAUCCCCACAGCCCUGACCCGCUGGACAGAAGAAUGCAAAGUUCUCGAUGCUGAGAGCAUGCAUGACUGUGUUUCAGUGGUUAAAGUGUCCAUUGUCAAUCACCUGGAAUUCCUGAGGGAUGAGGAGCUGGAAGAAAGGCGAGAGAAGCGCAGGAAACAACUGGCUGAGGAAGAAACAAAGAUAACUGAUAAAGGCAAAGAAGAUAAGGAGAACAGGGAUCAGAGUGCACAGUGUACUGCAUCUAAGUCAAAUGACUCCACUGAACAGAAUCUCUCAGAUGGGACGCCUAUGCCUGACAGCUACCCAACAACCCCAUCUUCAACUGAUGCAGCUACAUCUGAGUCCAAGGAGACCCUUGGCACUCUGCAAUCCUCACAACAGCAACCAACACUCCCAACCCCACCAGCUUUGGGAGAGGUUCCUCAGGAGCUGCAGUCUCCAGCUGGAGAAGGGGGCAGCUCUACACAGCUAUUGAUGCCUGUAGAGCCAGAGGAAUUGGGUCCCACAAGGCCAAGUGGGGAAGCAGAAACAACUCAGAUGGAGUUAUCCCCAGCUCCCACUAUAACCUCACUUUCCCCAGAGAGAGCUGAGGAUUCUGAUGCACUGACGGCUGUCAGCAGUCAGCUAGAAGGCUCUCCUAUGGAUACAAGCAGCCUGGCUUCCUGUACCUUAGAGGAGGCUGUGGGUGACACUUCAGCAGCUGGCAGUUCUGAGCAGCCCAGAGCAGGCAGCUCCACUCCUGGGGAUGCCCCACCAGCUGUGGCGGAAGUGCAAGGCAGGAGUGAUGGGUCAGGGGAAUCUGCCCAGCCACCUGAGGACAGCUCCCCACCUGCAUCCUCUGAGAGCUCUUCCACCAGAGAUUCUGCCGUGGCCAUUUCUGGAGCAGAUUCCCGAGGAAUCCUAGAAGAGCCGUUGCCUUCAACAAGCAGUGAAGAAGAAGAUCCCCUUGCGGGUAUCAGUCUCCCUGAAGGUGUGGACCCCUCUUUUCUGGCUGCCCUGCCUGAUGACAUCCGUCGGGAAGUUCUACAGAACCAGCUAGGCAUUCGUCCACCAACCCGGACUGCCCCCUCCACAAAUAGCUCAGCGCCUGCAGUGGUGGGGAAUCCUGGUGUGACUGAAGUGAGCCCUGAGUUUCUGGCUGCCCUGCCUCCAGCCAUUCAGGAGGAAGUACUGGCACAGCAGAGAGCUGAGCAGCAGCGACGAGAACUAGCACAGAAUGCCAGCUCAGACACCCCUAUGGACCCUGUGACCUUCAUCCAGACUCUGCCCUCAGACCUGCGCCGUAGUGUCCUAGAGGAUAUGGAGGACAGUGUGUUAGCUGUGAUGCCACCUGACAUUGCAGCUGAGGCUCAAGCCCUGAGACGAGAGCAAGAAGCCCGGCAGCGACAGCUCAUGCAUGAGCGUCUGUUUGGGCACAGUAGCACCUCCGCACUCUCUGCUAUUCUCCGAAGCCCGGCUUUCACCAGUCGCUUAAGUGGCAACCGUGGGGUCCAGUAUACUCGCCUUGCUGUGCAGAGAGGUGGCACCUUCCAGAUGGGGGGUAGCAGCAGCCAUAACAGGCCUUCUGGCAGUAAUGUAGAUACUCUCCUCCGCCUCCGAGGACGGCUCCUUCUGGACCACGAAGCCCUUUCUUGUCUCUUGGUCCUACUUUUUGUGGAUGAGCCAAAGCUCAAUACUAGCCGUCUACACCGAGUACUGAGAAAUCUCUGCUACCAUGCCCAGACCCGCCACUGGGUCAUCCGCAGUCUGCUCUCCAUCUUGCAGCGCAGCAGUGAGAGUGAGCUAUGCAUUGAAACACCCAAACUCACUACAAGUGAGGAAAAGGGCAAAAAGUCGAGCAAGAGCUGUGGGUCAAGUAGCCAUGAGAACCGUCCCCUGGACCUGCUACACAAGAUGGAGUCAAAGAGCUCCAACCAGCUUUCCUGGCUCUCAGUAUCCAUGGAUGCAGCCCUAGGCUGCAGGACUAAUAUAUUUCAGAUCCAGCGUUCAGGGGGGCGUAAACAUACCGAGAAGCAUGCAAGCGGUGGCUCCACCGUCCACAUCCAUCCCCAAGCUGCUCCUGUUGUCUGCAGACACGUUUUGGAUACACUCAUUCAAUUGGCCAAGGUAUUUCCCAGCCACUUCACACAGCAGCGGACCAAAGAAACAAACUGUGAGAGUGAUCGGGAAAGGGGCAAUAAGGCCUGUAGCCCAUGCUCCUCACAGUCCUCCAGCAGUGGCAUUUGCACAGACUUCUGGGACUUAUUGGUAAAACUGGACAACAUGAAUGUCAGCCGGAAAGGCAAGAACUCCGUGAAGUCAGUGCCAGUGAGCGCUGGCGGUGAGGGGGAAACCUCUCCAUACAGCCUCGAGGCCUCUCCACUGGGGCAGCUCAUGAACAUGUUGUCACACCCAGUCAUCCGCCGGAGCUCUCUCUUAACUGAGAAACUCCUCAGACUCCUUUCUCUCAUCUCAAUUGCUCUCCCAGAAAACAAGGUGUCAGAAGCACAGGCUAAUUCUGGCAGCGGUGCUUCCUCCACCACCACUGCCACCUCAACCACAUCUACCACCACCACCACUGCCGCCUCCACCACGCCCACACCCCCUACUGCACCCACCCCUGUCACUUCUGCUCCAGCCCUGGUUGCUGCCACGGCUAUUUCCACCAUUGUCGUAGCUGCUUCGACCACAGUGACUACCCCCACGACUGCUACCACUACUGUUUCAAUUUCUCCCACUACUAAGGGCAGCAAAUCUCCAGCGAAGGUGAGUGAUGGGGGCAGCAGCAGUACAGACUUUAAGAUGGUGUCCUCUGGCCUCACUGAAAACCAGCUACAGCUCUCUGUAGAGGUGUUGACAUCCCACUCUUGUUCUGAGGAAGGCUUAGAGGAUGCAGCCAACGUACUACUGCAGCUCUCCCGGGGGGACUCUGGGACCCGGGACACUGUUCUCAAGCUGCUACUGAAUGGAGCCCGCCAUCUGGGUUAUACCCUUUGUAAACAAAUAGGUACCCUGCUGGCCGAGCUGCGGGAAUACAACCUCGAGCAGCAGCGGCGAGCCCAAUGUGAAACCCUCUCUCCUGAUGGCCUGCCUGAGGAGCAGCCACAGACCACCAAGCUGAAGGGCAAAAUGCAGAGCAGGUUUGACAUGGCUGAGAAUGUGGUAAUUGUGGCAUCUCAGAAGCGACCUUUGGGUGGCCGGGAGCUCCAGCUGCCUUCUAUGUCCAUGUUGACAUCCAAGACAUCUACCCAGAAGUUCUUCUUGAGGGUACUACAGGUCAUCAUCCAGCUCCGGGACGACACGCGCCGGGCUAACAAGAAAGCCAAGCAGACAGGCAGGCUAGGUUCCUCCGGUUUAGGCUCAGCUAGCAGCAUCCAGGCAGCUGUUCGGCAGCUGGAGGCUGAGGCUGAUGCCAUUAUACAAAUGGUACGUGAGGGUCAAAGGGCGCGGAGACAGCAACAAGCAGCAACGUCGGAGUCUAGCCAGUCAGAGGCGUCUGUCCGGAGGGAGGAAUCACCCAUGGAUGUGGACCAGCCAUCUCCCAGUGCUCAAGAUACUCAAUCCAUUGCCUCCGAUGGAACCCCACAGGGGGAGAAGGAAAAGGAAGAAAGACCACCUGAGUUACCCCUGCUCAGCGAGCAGCUGAGUUUGGACGAGCUGUGGGACAUGCUUGGGGAGUGUCUAAAGGAACUAGAGGAAUCCCAUGACCAGCAUGCGGUGCUAGUGCUACAGCCUGCUGUCGAGGCCUUCUUUCUGGUCCAUGCCACAGAGCGGGAGAGCAAGCCUCCUGUCCGAGACACCCGUGAGAGCCAGCUGGCACACAUCAAGGACGAGCCUCCUCCACUCUCCCCUGCCCCCUUAACCCCAGCCACGCCUUCCUCCCUUGACCCAUUCUUCUCCCGGGAGCCCUCAUCUAUGCACAUCUCCUCAAGCCUGCCCCCUGACACACAGAAGUUCCUUCGCUUUGCAGAGACUCACCGCACUGUGUUAAACCAGAUCCUACGGCAGUCCACGACCCACCUUGCUGAUGGGCCUUUUGCUGUCCUGGUAGACUACAUUCGUGUCCUCGACUUUGAUGUCAAGCGCAAAUAUUUCCGCCAAGAGCUGGAGCGUUUAGAUGAGGGGCUCCGGAAAGAAGACAUGGCUGUGCAUGUCCGUCGUGACCAUGUGUUUGAAGACUCCUAUCGUGAGCUGCAUCGCAAAUCCCCCGAAGAAAUGAAGAAUCGAUUGUAUAUAGUAUUUGAAGGAGAAGAAGGGCAGGAUGCUGGUGGGCUCCUGCGGGAGUGGUAUAUGAUCAUCUCUCGAGAGAUGUUUAACCCUAUGUAUGCCUUGUUCCGUACCUCACCUGGUGAUCGAGUCACCUACACCAUCAAUCCAUCUUCCCACUGCAACCCCAACCACCUCAGCUACUUCAAGUUUGUCGGACGCAUUGUGGCCAAAGCUGUAUAUGACAACCGUCUUCUGGAGUGCUACUUUACUCGAUCCUUUUACAAACACAUCUUGGGCAAGUCAGUCAGAUAUACAGAUAUGGAGAGUGAAGAUUACCACUUCUACCAAGGUCUGGUUUAUCUGCUGGAAAAUGAUGUCUCCACACUAGGCUAUGACCUCACCUUCAGCACUGAGGUCCAAGAGUUUGGAGUUUGUGAAGUUCGUGACCUCAAACCCAAUGGGGCCAACAUCUUGGUAACAGAGGAGAAUAAGAAGGAGUAUGUACACCUGGUAUGCCAGAUGAGAAUGACAGGAGCCAUCCGCAAGCAGUUGGCGGCUUUCUUAGAAGGCUUCUAUGAGAUCAUUCCAAAGCGCCUCAUUUCCAUCUUCACUGAGCAGGAGUUAGAGCUGCUUAUAUCAGGACUGCCCACCAUUGACAUCGAUGAUCUGAAAUCCAACACUGAAUACCACAAGUACCAGUCCAACUCUAUUCAGAUCCAGUGGUUCUGGAGAGCAUUGCGUUCUUUCGAUCAAGCUGACCGUGCCAAGUUCCUCCAGUUUGUCACAGGUACUUCCAAGGUACCCCUGCAAGGCUUUGCUGCCCUCGAAGGCAUGAAUGGCAUUCAGAAGUUUCAGAUCCAUCGAGAUGACAGGUCCACAGAUCGCCUGCCUUCAGCUCACACAUGUUUUAAUCAGCUGGAUCUGCCUGCCUAUGAGAGCUUUGAGAAGCUCCGCCACAUGCUACUGUUGGCUAUCCAGGAGUGCUCUGAAGGCUUUGGGCUGGCCUAAUAAGGCCCUGCCCAACUCCGUGGGGUUUUUUUUACCAUUGUUGGACCUGGGGAGGGGGGAGUUAAAAAAAGAACCAGAAAGAAAUUGUCAAAAACCAAUAAAUGAAAUCCACCAACUCACCGUGUGUGUCCCAGCUGCCCCAUCUUCCCCAGCGCAUACCUGUUCCUCUUCUCAUUCUCUCCCCGCCGCCUGUUUCCUCACCUUCUCUCCCCUUUCCAUGCCGUCCAUGAUCCCCACCCCAUGUGUUUUAAAAAGGCAGUAGCCUUUGCAGGGACCUGUCUGUCCCAACUGUUUGAACAGUGUGCUCCUCAGAUUCUGUGUUCAGAAGGAUUUGCUGCAUUGAGACUUGAAACCUUUGGAUAGGGGAAAAAAUUAUAUAUAUAUAUAUUUUUUUGUUCUGUUUGCAUUUCUUAAUUUGUGCUUGGAAUGUGUUGAUGUGCACAGCUAAUGAUUCAAUGCGAGACAAGAUUGGCGUCUGUGUUGUGGAGGUUUCAAAUAAAGAGCACUCUUCAUAACUCACUUUUCACAAUGGAGUUUUUUUCAAACUUAAAAAAAAAAACAAAAAACUCUUAAGCACAUGCUAGGCAUCUGGAGAAAAGAUGGAUUCUCCAGGAAACCAUCCCUGCCCUACCCGCUUGCCCACCUGCCUCCACCACUGGUGCAACUUCCUCCUUCAGAGUCAGUUUCUGCAGUCAGGAGAGAUGAGCAGUUCACCAGGAAUUGGGGGUGGGGGCAUCUGUUUUUUUUUUUUAGAAUGGGAGCUGCACUUGGGGAUGGUGAUGGUGUUAGAGAUUGCAGCCCAGGACAAAGCAUCACCUUGCUCAAGGGGAACAAACUGCAGCAGGUUGUACAAAACAUUCAGAGAGCUCACUUGACCCAACCGAGGGUUUUACUUGGUGAGCCUUUCUAGUAGUCUUGAGUCUGGGGCUCAGUUUUAGAUUUUUAUUUCAUUAAUGUUUGUUUAUUUCUAAUAAAUUUUAAUAAGCGAGUAAUUUAACUAGGUCGCCAGAAGACCAUUAUUUUUGUUUGUCUAUUUUUGUUGUCGUCACUCCCUCUCUCGUCAUCUGUCUGCCAGUCUGUUCACAGAUCACCUUGUAGUCCCUUGUGGUUUUUACUCCAUCCAGUGCUUAAAGCUGAUCUAAGGACUUCGAUGGUUCCAGCCUUCAAAGAAAAAAUAAUUUAAUAAAAAUUUAGUUAGAAAAAAUAACCCCAA